AAAGAGGCUUUCUCACCAGCCAAAGUUCAGGUACUGCCCCUGUCUGAGUUUGGACAUGUGGCCCACAGAUGCCAGCUGGGGGCUGGAAUACUGUACCUUGAUCUUAGGGCCUGGAAAAAUCAGGUAGGUAACUCUCUGGUCCUAGGUGGAGGUGUAGGGGAGGUUGGGCCAGGGAUGCCUUCACUGUGUCUCUCUGGUCUUGCCACCCCAGACCGAGGGACACACAGGCACUGCUGUCUGCAACACAAGCAAUGGACCUGCGGAGGCGAGACUACCACAUGGAACGGCCGCUGCUGAACCAGGAGCAUUUGGAGGAGCUGGGGCGCUGGGGCUCAGCACCUAGGACCCACCAGUGGCGGACCUGGUUGCAGUGCUCCCGUGCUCGGGCCUAUGCCCUUCUGCUCCAACACCUCCCGGUUUUGGUCUGGUUACCCCGGUAUCCUGUGCGUGACUGGCUCCUGGGUGACCUGUUAUCCGGCCUGAGUGUGGCCAUCAUGCAGCUUCCGCAGGGCUUGGCCUACGCCCUCCUGGCUGGAUUGCCCCCCGUGUUUGGCCUCUAUAGCUCCUUCUACCCUGUCUUCAUCUACUUCCUGUUUGGCACUUCCCGGCACAUCUCCGUGGGGACCUUUGCUGUCAUGUCUGUGAUGGUGGGCAGUGUGACAGAAUCCCUGGCCCCGCAGGCCUUGAACGACUCCAUGAUCAAUGAGACAGCCAGAGAUGCUGCCCGGGUACAGGUGGCCUCCACACUCAGUGUCCUGGUUGGCCUCUUCCAGGUGGGGCUGGGCCUGAUCCACUUCGGCUUCGUGGUCACCUACCUGUCAGAACCUCUUGUCCGAGGCUAUACCACAGCUGCAGCUGUGCAGGUCUUCGUCUCACAGCUCAAGUAUGUGUUUGGCCUCCAUCUGAGCAGCCACUCUGGGCCACUGUCCCUCAUCUAUACAGUGCUGGAGGUCUGCUGGAAGCUGCCCCAGAGCAAGGUUGGCACCGUGGUCACUGCAGCUGUGGCUGGGGUGGUGCUCGUGGUGGUGAAGCUGUUGAAUGACAAGCUGCAGCAGCAGCUGCCCAUGCCGAUACCCGGGGAGCUGCUCACGCUCAUCGGGGCCACAGGCAUCUCCUAUGGCAUGGGUCUAAAGCACAGAUUUGAGGUAGAUGUCGUGGGCAACAUCCCUGCAGGGCUGGUGCCCCCAGUGGCCCCCAACACCCAGCUGUUCUCAAAGCUCGUGGGCAGCGCCUUCACCAUCGCUGUGGUUGGGUUUGCCAUUGCCAUCUCACUGGGGAAGAUCUUCGCCCUGAGGCACGGCUACCGGGUGGACAGCAACCAGGAGCUGGUGGCCCUGGGCCUCAGUAACCUUAUCGGAGGCAUCUUCCAGUGCUUCCCCGUGAGUUGCUCUAUGUCUCGGAGCCUGGUACAGGAGAGCACCGGGGGCAACUCGCAGGUUGCUGGAGCCAUCUCUUCCCUUUUCAUCCUCCUCAUCAUUGUCAAACUUGGGGAACUCUUCCAUGACCUGCCCAAGGCGGUCCUGGCAGCCAUCAUCAUUGUGAACCUGAAGGGCAUGCUGAGGCAGCUCAGCGACAUGCGCUCCCUCUGGAAGGCCAAUCGGGCGGAUCUGCUUAUCUGGCUGGUGACCUUCACGGCCACCAUCUUGCUGAACCUGGACCUUGGCUUGGUGGUUGCGGUCAUCUUCUCCCUGCUGCUCGUGGUGGUCCGGACACAGAUGCCCCACUACUCUGUCCUGGGGCAGGUGCCAGACACGGAUAUUUACAGAGAUGUGGCAGAGUACUCAGAGGCCAAGGAAGUCCGGGGGGUGAAGGUCUUCCGCUCCUCGGCCACCGUGUACUUUGCCAAUGCUGAGUUCUACAGUGAUGCGCUGAAGCAGAGGUGUGGUGUGGAUGUCGACUUCCUCAUCUCCCAGAAGAAGAAACUGCUCAAGAAGCAGGAGCAGCUGAAGCUGAAGCAACUGCAGAAAGAGGAGAAGCUUCGGAAACAGGCUGCCUCCCCCAAGGGCGCCUCAGUUUCCAUUAAUGUCAACACCAGCCUUGAAGACAUGAGGAGCAACAACGUUGAGGACUGCAAGAUGAUGCAGGUGAGCUCAGGAGAUAAGAUGGAAGAUGCAACAGCCAAUGGUCAAGAAGACUCCAAGGCCCCAGAUGGGUCCACACUGAAGGCCCUGGGCCUGCCUCAGCCAGACUUCCACAGCCUCAUCCUGGACCUGGGUGCCCUCUCCUUUGUGGACACUGUGUGCCUCAAGAGCCUGAAGAAUAUUUUCCAUGACUUCCGGGAGAUUGAGGUGGAGGUGUACAUGGCGGCCUGCCACAGCCCUGUGGUCAGCCAGCUUGAGGCUGGGCACUUCUUCGAUGCAUCCAUCACCAAGAAGCAUCUCUUUGCCUCUGUCCAUGAUGCUGUCACCUUUGCCCUCCAACACCCGAGGCCUGUCCCCGACAGCCCUGUUUCGGUCACCAGACUCUGAACAUGCUACAUCCUGCCCAAGACUGCACCUCUGGAGGUGCAGGGCACCCUUGAGAAGCCCCUCACCCCUAGGCCGCCUCCAGGUGCUACCCAGGAGUCCCCUCCAUGUACACACACACAACUCAGGGAAGGAGGUCCUGGGACUCCAAGUUCAGCGCUCCAGGUCUGGGACAGGGCCUGCAUGCAGUCAGGCUGGCAGUGGCGCGGUACAGGGAGGGAACUGGUGCAUAUUUUAGCCUCAGGAAUAAAGAUUUGUCUGCUCAA